GCUUCUGCCCUGGAGCGCGGUCGGGAGUAAAAUCGCAGGAGUGGGAGGGUAGCGAGCCAGCUGGAUUCCGAGCCGCGGAGCGCGCUGGCUUUGCUCCGCCUGAUGACUCCAGAGCGCGGGUCCAAGCGCCGCCCAUGCAGCACCCCUGAGCUCCGGGGAAGGAGAGUUAAUGAAAAAACACUUAACCGUCUCCGCUGCGGAGAGUCAUGAGCUGUCUGGAUGUUAUGUACCAAGUCUAUGGUCCUCCGCAGCCCUACUUCGCAGCCGCCUACACCCCCUACCACCAGAAACUAGCCUAUUAUUCCAAAAUGCAGGAAGCGCAGGAGUGCAAUGCCAGCCCCAGCAGCAGUGGCAGCGGCAGCUCCUCAUUUUCCAGCCAAACCCCAGCCAGUAUAAAAGAGGAAGAAGGCAGCCCAGAGAAAGAGCGCCCACCAGAGGCAGAGUACAUCAACUCCCGCUGCGUCCUCUUCACUUAUUUCCAGGGGGACAUCAGCUCCGUGGUGGAUGAACAUUUCAGCAGGGCCCUGAGCCAACCCAGCAGCUACUCUCCUAGCUGUACCAGCAGCAAAGCACCAAGGAGCUCUGGGCCCUGGCGAGACUGCUCCUUCCCGAUGAGCCAGCGCAGCUUCCCCGCCUCCUUCUGGAAUAGCGCGUACCAGGCGCCAGUGCCCCCGCCGCUGGGCAGCCCUCUGGCCACCGCGCACUCGGAGCUGCCCUUCGCCGCCGCCGACCCCUACUCGCCCGCCGCGCUGCAUGGCCACCUGCACCAGGGCGCCACGGAGCCCUGGCACCACGCGCACCCGCACCACGCGCACCCGCAUCACCCCUACGCCCUGGGCGGCGCCCUCGGCGCCCAGGCCGCCCCCUACCCGCGCCCCGCCGCCGUGCACGAAGUCUACGCGCCGCACUUCGACCCGCGCUAUGGGCCGCUGCUGAUGCCAGCCGCCUCGGGGCGCCCGGCCCGCCUCGCAACCGCCCCGGCGCCCGCGCCCGGCAGUCCUCCCUGCGAGCUCUCCGGCAAAGGCGAGCCGGCGGGCGCCGCGUGGGCCGGGCCCGGGGGACCCUUCGCGAGCCCCUCGGGGGACGUGGCCCAGGGUCUGGGCCUCAGCGUGGACUCAGGUUUGCAGCCUCAGGACAAAAGCAAGGAUGUGUACUGGUUUUAGACCGCCCACCUUCUUCCCUGUAGGUCUCUGCAUAGUGCAAUUGAUGGCACUCAGAGCUGAAAUGGAGUGGGUUUGUAACAGCUUCUGAUCUUGGUUUGCAGCUCGUCGUUAUUCCCUCUGUGGUGCAUCCCUCCUGAGCUGAUCUGCUGACCCAGGGUUUCCCCUUCCCCUUCCCUUCUGACCAGCCUUGGAGGCUCAGCAUCUGUGCCUCUCACUCCGUGGAUGAGGACAUGGGGGAAGGCAGAGACUUCAGACUUCUCAGUGUGUUGGGAAAACCAAAAACCACAACUACAGAAAUUCAUCUAAAAAUAAGUCCUGCUGCUGAAAGAGCAAAUCCAAAGACUGAGUUAUGUUUAAUGACUUUUGGCCGAAUCACUGGAAAUAUCUGUGGUGAGAUUGCUGAGUCAGGUGAUGUGAUAUCAUAAGCUUUCUUGGAACGGGGGAAAGAAAAUGAAACUUUUUGGUGUGAAUAUUUUUUAUGCUGAUGUGAAUUAUUUUGUUAGGUAGUGUGAUUAUAGCACUACUACUGUCAGAUUUUAAAUUGUAUGUGUACUUGCAUCUAAGACUGUGGUAGAGAAGUAAAGAGAAGUCAAUUCCUUCUUCCUCACCUCUCAGCCUCCAGAUCCCUUCCUGCCCAUCCCUUCCCUACAAUGCCCACUCCAGACGCAAAGAUACACUUUUUUCCUUUGGACUGUGAACAUGGAAGCCUCAGCCUGAAUGUGAGUGGCAAGUGGCUUAUCUGGAGCCACCUGCCCAAGUCUUACUAAAAUGCAGCUGUUGUUAGACAACUGUUGAAAACUCCAGAAAUACAUCACCCAAGGUGGCAGUUCUCAGUAUUUGGCAGAACAAUUGCAAUUGCACUGGGUAUAUUAUAUAUAUAUAUGUAUGCAUAUAUAUCAUAUUUUUUACAAGGAACAUUUUAUGAUGAAAGAAGAAACCCUUCUCUGCCUUCUCUCCCACGAAUUCUGUCCCUGUAUCCUCUGGAUGUAAAAAGCAAGGAGAGACCCCAACUGUCUCCAUGGAGAAGAACUAGGAAUCACCACAAGGGGAAGAAAUGUACAUGAAGUCUCCAUUACCUCGAAUUUUUUUCUCAGUCUCACUGGUUGUGAUUUGGUCACUUUAGUGUUGGGACAGGGGAAAGGGUCUGUGCGUGGGCAAAGCUGAAGGUGAUGAGGAAGAAGAGACGAACAUUAAAGAUGUCUAUUUACUAUGAGCUCACUGUGUUGUUUCAUAAAAAGAAAAUAAAUAACUUAGUUUUUUUCUAGUAGAAUAAAAUAA